GAGUGCAUCGCGUUCUUGCUGGAGGGCGGAUGCGCCCUGCCUUCCUCUGACUCGCUGGCGGCCUCGGAAACGCUACUCCCGCGGGAGAGCGCUCGUGGGACGGCCUGGGCCAGGCUGCUUGUCAGCCCCUGCGCUUCCCGGCAGUUUCCGCGUCCCUGUUUUCCCUGCGCGUCUUCUGAUUUCCACCAUGAGGACGUUUGGGUCGUGAUUUUCAUCUGCAUGUGGAGGAAACUGGGCCGCGCGCCGGGAGCCGCGCCUGCGGGUGCUCCGCCCCCAAGUGCCUGUGGGUUUGGUGCGGGCCUUGGGUUCAGUUCAGCUCGCUGUGACCUCGACUGAGCGCUGGAGGCUCCGCGGGCGGGAGCAGGAGGGCUGGAGCCGGCGCCUGCUGUGUGCCCGGCGCGGUAGUGAUGUGUGAGCCUCCCCGCAACUUCUGAGAAGGUGUGACCUUGUGUGGUCAGGAAGCCGAAGCUUGACGAGUUUUCAAGUACGUUUUCUCAGGUCCUGCAGCUGGGAGACGGCACAGGACACUAAACCAGAGCCCACCCACCUUUGGGUUCCUGUUGGACAUCGAUGGAGUGCUUGUGCGGGGCCACAGAGUGAUCCCUGCUGCUCUGAAAGCCUUCCGAAGGCUGGUGAACUCCCAGGGGCAGCUGCGGGUGCCCGUGGUUUUUGUUACAAAUGCUGGGAACAUCUUACAACACAGCAAAGCCCAGGAGCUGUCAGCCCUGCUGGGGUGCGAGGUGGAUGCAGACCAAGUUAUCCUCUCUCACAGCCCCAUGAAGCUCUUCUCCGAGUACCAUGAGAAGCGGAUGCUGGUGUCUGGACAGGGGCCCGUGAUGGAAAAUGCCCAGGGACUGGGCUUCCGAAAUGUCGUCACCGUGGAUGAGCUGCGGAUGGCCUUUCCUCUGCUUGACAUGGUGGACCUGGAGCGGCGGCUAAAGACCACGCCCCUCCCGAGGAAUGACUUCCCCCGCAUUGAAGGGGUGCUCCUCCUAGGGGAGCCGGUCCGCUGGGAGACCAGCCUGCAGCUGAUCAUGGAUGUCCUCCUCAGCAAUGGGAGCCCUGGGGCUGGCCUGGCAACACCCCCCUACCCCCACCUCCCCGUCCUAGCCAGCAACAUGGAUCUCCUGUGGAUGGCUGAAGCCAAGAUGCCCAGGUUUGGACAUGGCACCUUUCUGCUGUGCCUGGAAACCAUUUACCAGAAAGUGACGGGCAAGGAGCUGAGAUACGAGGGCCUGAUGGGCAAACCCAGCAUCCUCACUUACCAGUAUGCCGAGGACCUGAUCAGGCGACAGGCGGAGAGGCGGGGCUGGGCCGCCCCCAUCCGGAAGCUCUAUGCUGUGGGUGAUAACCCUAUGUCUGACGUAUACGGCGCCAACCUGUUCCACCAGUACCUGCAGAAGGCAACGCAUGAUGGGGCGCCAGAACUAGGGGCCGGGGGCACACGGCAGCAACAGCCCUCAGCAAGCCAGAGCUGCAUCUCCAUCCUGGUGUGUACAGGCGUCUACAAUCCCAGGAACCCACAGUCCACGGAGCCUGUCCUUGGAGGAGGGGAGCCUCCAUUCCACGGGCACCGAGACUUAUGCUUCAGUCCAGGGCUCAUGGAGGCCUCCCACGUGGUGAAUGACGUGAAUGAGGCUGUGCAGCUGGUCUUCCGCAAGGAGGGCUGGGCUUUGGAGUGAGGGCAGUGCGGUGGAGGUGAGGGGGUGAGCCUGGACCUGUGGGCGAGUCCCAUUGGCUGGGCUCUGGCCUGAUCACUGGGCUCAGGUCAGGGCUUGGUUCCCUUGCCACCCUUCUUGCUGCCCCAUGAGUGUGGCAUUACUGGUCACUUGGAAGAAGACAGUGACUCUUUUUCCCUGCUGGGUAGCAUUUUGUAUGGAACGGUUGGAAUUUUCUGGGCCCAGUUCCCACGUGCCUUUCGUGGCAGUCUAACCUCAGGCCAUUCUCUUCCCCUGUGUGCCUCAGUGUCCUUCUCAUUUCAGUAGGGACUUCUGAAAUGGGGGAGGCAGUGUGGAAUACUGUGGAUGUCUGUGCAGAGCCUUUGCCGGCACUGAAGGCAUGCAGCCUGUCGGCAGAGUGUCUUAACACCAGAUGCUACUUUUUACUGUAUUGUAGUUUAUUGCCCGGAGAUGUGGGGCUUUUUUUUUAAAUAAAAUAAUCAUAAUAAAUGUUCAUGAUGCUGA